ACACGCGCAGCCAGCCGGCCGCCUCCCGCGCCCAAGCGCGCCGCUCUGCUGUGCCCUGCGCCCUUGCCCCGCGCCAGCUUCUGCGCCCGCAGCCCGCCCGGCGCCCCCGGUGACCGUGACCCUGCCCUGGGCGCGGGGCGGAGCAGGCAUGUCCCGCCCGGGGACCGCUACCCCAGCGCUGGCCCUGGUGCUCCUGGCAGUGACCCUGGCCGGGGUCGGAGCCCAGGGCGCAGCCCUCGAGGACCCUGAUUAUUACGGGCAGGAGAUCUGGAGCCGGGAGCCCUACUACGCGCGCCCGGAGCCCGAGCUCGAGACCUUCUCUCCGCCGCUGCCUGCGGGGCCCGGGGAGGAGUGGGAGCGGCGCCCGCAGGAGCCCAGGCCGCCCAAGAGGGCCACCAAGCCCAAGAAAGCUCCCAAGAGGGAGAAGUCGGCUCCGGAGCCGCCUCCACCAGGUAAACACAGCAACAAAAAAGUUAUGAGAACCAAGAGCUCUGAGAAGGCUGCCAACGAUGAUCACAGUGUCCGUGUGGCCCGUGAAGAUGUCAGAGAGAGUUGCCCACCUCUUGGUCUGGAAACCUUAAAAAUCACAGACUUCCAGCUCCAUGCCUCCACGGUGAAGCGCUAUGGCCUGGGGGCACAUCGAGGGAGACUCAACAUCCAGGCGGGCAUUAAUGAAAAUGAUUUUUAUGACGGAGCGUGGUGCGCGGGAAGAAAUGACCUCCAGCAGUGGAUUGAAGUGGAUGCUCGGCGCCUGACCAGAUUCACUGGUGUCAUCACUCAAGGGAGGAACUCCCUCUGGCUGAGUGACUGGGUGACAUCCUAUAAGGUCAUGGUGAGCAAUGACAGCCACACGUGGGUCACUGUUAAGAAUGGAUCUGGAGACAUGAUAUUUGAGGGAAACAGUGAGAAGGAGAUCCCUGUUCUCAAUGAGCUACCCGUCCCCAUGGUGGCCCGCUACAUCCGCAUAAACCCUCAGUCCUGGUUUGAUAAUGGGAGCAUCUGCAUGAGAAUGGAGAUCCUGGGCUGCCCACUGCCAGAUCCUAAUAAUUAUUAUCACCGCCGGAACGAGAUGACCACCACUGAUGACCUGGAUUUUAAGCACCACAAUUAUAAGGAAAUGCGCCAGUUGAUGAAAGUUGUGAAUGAAAUGUGUCCCAAUAUCACCAGAAUUUACAACAUUGGAAAAAGCCACCAGGGCCUGAAGCUGUAUGCUGUGGAGAUCUCAGAUCACCCUGGGGAGCAUGAAGUCGGUGAGCCCGAGUUCCACUACAUCGCGGGGGCCCACGGCAAUGAGGUGCUGGGCCGGGAGCUGCUGCUGCUGCUGGUGCAGUUCGUGUGUCAGGAGUACUUGGCCCGGAAUGCGCGCAUCGUCCACCUGGUGGAGGAGACGCGGAUUCACGUCCUCCCCUCCCUCAACCCCGAUGGCUACGAGAAGGCCUACGAAGGGGGCUCGGAGCUGGGAGGCUGGUCCCUGGGACGCUGGACCCACGAUGGAAUUGACAUCAACAACAACUUUCCUGAUUUAAACACGCUGCUCUGGGAGGCAGAGGAUCGACAGAAUGUCCCCAGGAAAGUUCCCAAUCACUAUAUUGCAAUCCCUGAGUGGUUUCUGUCGGAAAAUGCCACGGUGGCUGCCGAGACCAGAGCAGUCAUAGCCUGGAUGGAAAAAAUCCCUUUUGUGCUGGGCGGCAACCUGCAGGGCGGCGAGCUGGUGGUGGCGUACCCCUACGACCUGGUGCGGUCCCCCUGGAAGACGCAGGAACACACCCCCACCCCCGACGACCACGUGUUCCGCUGGCUGGCCUACUCCUAUGCCUCCACACACCGCCUCAUGACAGACGCCCGGAGGAGGGUGUGCCACACGGAGGACUUCCAGAAGGAGGAGGGCACUGUCAAUGGGGCCUCCUGGCACACCGUCGCUGGAAGUCUGAACGAUUUCAGCUACCUUCAUACAAACUGCUUCGAACUGUCCAUCUACGUGGGCUGUGAUAAAUACCCACAUGAGAGCCAGCUGCCCGAGGAGUGGGAGAAUAACCGGGAAUCUCUGAUCGUGUUCAUGGAGCAGGUUCAUCGUGGCAUUAAAGGCUUGGUGAGAGAUUCACAUGGAAAAGGAAUCCCAAACGCCAUUAUCUCCGUAGAAGGCAUUAACCAUGACAUCCGAACAGGGAGGAGAGGCUCCUUCUCUGCAAACUGUUCCCAUGAUCCUGUCGUGCCAACAAAAGAUCCCAUUCCACCUGCCAGGAAGCAGACUUUGGGACAUUAGGAUGAGGCGAGGCUGGGGUUCAGACCUGGCCCAUGUAUCCUUCAUUGCCAGGCUCCCUAGCAGUGGGCCUGGCAUAAAAGACCAAAUAUGUAAAUGGGGGAAAUGUGUCUAAAAUGCCACAAAAUAGUAGAUUGCUGUGUAAUGCCAUAAAUUGCAUUUUUCCCAUCUAGUUACUGAUUUCUUUGCUCAAUAAUAUUUUCUGAACAUUCCUACCAUUUGUCACUGAUCUUAUAGCCAUGAACCAUGAGGCUUCACACUGAAUACCAUGGAAUUUUGUACGUAGUAGCCCCUCAUAGGUGUUCAUUUUUUUCAUAUAUUUAUUCACUAUUCCUUAAUUAAUUCAGCAAAUGUAGAUUGCAUAGCUGGAAUGUGCCAGAGACCACGCAGAGUGUUGGCGAUCAUUAUGCAUGAAAGGCUGUGUGAUGUGGUUCUGCAUAGGAUUUGUAUUUUAAACAUUACAAAUGAAGCUCCUUUGAAAUGACAAUUCUAAAAGAGCCUAGAACAUUCCUUGACUAUUUAGUGCUUUGUAUGCAAUGUGAGAAAAUGUGGGAGUUUUGAACUGAGUGGGAGAUAAAAAGACCCUGGGGCCUCAUAAGCCAAGAUAGAAUACUUUGCCUAAUGGGUGCUGAGUUUCAAGCCCCUGCAAUCAAUGAGACAGUUUUGAUGAGCUAAUGGGAAAUGCAUCUCCCUCCCUUGAUUUUCCCCUCUAUAAAUAAUUUCCCAGUGUAUUCUCAUGACAGAUAAACUCCAUACUUUACACACGGCUCUUUGUUCUGUUUCAGAAUCUUUCGGUUCUCAAGAAAAGCUCUGAAUUUGCCUUGAUUUCUAUCUGAGGUUUAUGUGAUCUGACAAGUUUUAUUUCGGGAUGGAUUUUGCAUAAAAUAAACAGGGGUAUUAAAUGGAAUUCCACAGGGAGGGAAGCUGGUAGGAAUGCUUUGAGUUAGAUGCAUAUCAGUAUGUUGGACAGACACCCGGCUCACCGUUCCACAUGCCUGUCCUUUGCUUGGUGGGUACUGAACUGACCUGCUCCUGUGUGGACAUUCUUUGGGCCUGAGUUGCCCCUUCUGCCCACGUAUAGGAGAUGUGUCAGGGUGGCGGGAGAAAUUAUAAGGAAAGACGCAAACCUUCUUAGAAGGUCAGGACGUUUUGCAAAACUUCGGAAGGGCAAAGGGUAGAUAACAAGGGAAUGUAAAGGAAUUUAUUUGGAUGAAUUUGUUUACUUAUGUCUCCAGAUAUCAACCUUUGAUCAUUUGCACACAGGACUGCUCUCUACUCGGGGGGUCGACAAUGUUAAUUACCCACAAAUUGUGUUUGCUCCAAGCCUUUGUCAUUAAAUCUGUACUAAAUAAAUACAAACAUCUCUGGC